UCAUUGCCAAUUGCAGCUCAACUUGAAUUUCACAGCCCGAUGUGAGAUGCGUCUCUGCUGAUCUGAGCCUGUCCUGCAGCAUGGACCUGCAACUUUCCUGAAGCAUCUCCAGGGCUGGAUGCCAUGAGAACCUGGUGCCUGCCUCAGCCCUAGCUCUGGGGAAAUGAAAGCCAGGCUGGGGUUCAAAUGAGGGCAGUUUCCCUUCCUGUGGGCUGCUGAUGGAACAACCCCAUGACGAGAAGGACCCAGCCUCCAAGCGGCCACACCCUGUGUGUCUCUUUGUCCUGCCGGCACUGAGGACUCAUCCAUCUGCACAGCUGGGGCCCCUGGGAGGAGACGCCAUGAUCCCCACCCUCACGGCUCUGCUCUGCCUCGGGCUGAGUCUGGGCCCCAGGACCCACAUGCAGGCAGGGCCCCUCCCCAAACCCACCCUCUGGGCUGAGCCAGGCUCUGUGAUCAGCUGGGGGAACUCUGUGACCAUCUGGUGUCAGGGGACCCUGGAGGCUCGGGAGUACCGUCUGGAUAAAGAGGAAAGCCCAGCACCCUGGGACAGACAGAACCCACUGGAGCCCAAGAACAAGGCCAGAUUCUCCAUCCCAUCCAUGACAGAGGACUAUGCAGGGAGAUACCGCUGUUACUAUCGCAGCCCUGUAGGCUGGUCACAGCCCAGUGACCCCCUGGAGCUGGUGAUGACAGGAGCCUACAGUAAACCCACCCUUUCAGCCCUGCCGAGUCCUCUUGUGACCUCAGGAAAGAGCGUGACCCUGCUGUGUCAGUCACGGAGCCCAAUGGACACUUUUCUUCUGAUCAAGGAGCGGGCAGCCCAUCCCCUACUGCAUCUGAGAUCAGAGCACGGAGCUCAGCAGCACCAGGCUGAAUUCCCCAUGAGUCCUGUGACCUCAGUGCACGGGGGGACCUACAGGUGCUUCAGCUCACACGGCUUCUCCCACUACCUGCUGUCACACCCCAGUGACCCCCUGGAGCUCAUAGUCUCAGGAUCCUUGGAGGGUCCCAGGCCCUCACCCACAAGGUCCGUCUCAACAGCUGCAGGCCCUGAGGACCAGCCCCUCAUGCCUACAGGGUCAGUCCCCCACAGUGGUCUGAGAAGGCACUGGGAGGUACUGAUCGGGGUCUUGGUGGUCUCCAUCCUGCUUCUCUCCCUCCUCCUCUUCCUCCUCCUCCAACACUGGCGUCAGGGAAAACACAGGACAUUGGCCCAGAGACAGGCUGAUUUCCAACGUCCUCCAGGGGCUGCCGAGCCAGAGCCCAAGGACGGGGGCCUACAGAGGAGGUCCAGCCCAGCUGCUGACGUCCAGGGAGAAAACUUCUCAGGUGCUGCCGUGAAGAACACACAGCCUGAGGACGGGGUGGAAAUGGACACUCGGCAGAGCCCACACGAUGAAGACCCCCAGGCAGUGACGUAUGCCAAGGUGAAACACUCCAGACCUAGGAGAGAAAUGGCCUCUCCUCCCUCCCCACUGUCUGGGGAAUUCCUGGACACAAAGGACAGACAGGCAGAAGAGGACAGACAGAUGGACACUGAGGCUGCUGCAUCUGAAGCCCCCCAGGAUGUGACCUACGCCCGGCUGCACAGCUUUACCCUCAGACAGAAGGCAACUGAGCCUCCUCCAUCCCAGGAAGGGGCCUCUCCAGCUGAGCCCAGUGUCUAUGCCACUCUGGCCAUCCACUAAUCCAGGGGGGACCCAGACCCCACAAGCCAUGGAGACUCAGGACCCCAGAAGGCAUGGAAGCUGCCUCCAGUAGACAUCACUGAACCCCAGCCAGCCCAGACCCCUGACACAGACCACUAGAAGAUUCCGGGAACGUUGGGAGUCACCUGAUUCUGCAAAGAUAAAUAAUAUCCCUGCAUUAUCAAAAUAAAGUAGCAGACCUCUCAAUUCACAAUGAGUUAACUGAUAAAACAAAACAGAAGUCAGACAAUGUUUUAAAUUGAAUGAUCAUGUAAAUAUUACACAUCAAACCAAUGACAUGGGAAAAUGGGAGCUUCUAAUGAGGACAAACAAAAAAUAGAGAAAAAUUAAUAAAGUCAAAAUGUUUAUUCUUGAAAACAUUAAUGAUACAUGAAUCUUGGCCACAAUGAGAAAAAUAAAAAUGAAAAAAGAGCAGGCAUCCAUUUCCAUACAGGAACAAAAUAGGAGGCAGCACUACAGACCCUACACACAGCUUUACAGAGGUGAAAGAAAACUGUCAGCAAUUCUAUGCUGACAUAACAGAAAAUGUAGAUGAGAUAGAUGAAAUACGAAAAAUUACAGUUUACUUAAUGAACAUAAGGAUAAAUAGAAAAACUGAAUCAUCAUACAUAAACAUAUAUAAAAUGCAUUGAUCCUGUAAUCAAAAAUGUUCCCACAAAGUAAAUGCCACUUCAGCAA